GCCAGAAUCCAGCACUCCAAGCACUGCUGUCUUCUCACAGAGUCUUGAAGCCAGAGCAGCGCCAGGAUGUCACGGGAGCUGGCCCCACUGCUGCUUCUCCUCCUCUCCAUCCACAGCGCCCUGGCCAUGAGGAUCUGCUCCUUCAACGUCAGGUCCUUUGGGGAAAGCAAGCAGGAAGACAAGAAUGCCAUGGAUGUCAUUGUGAAGGUCAUCAAACGCUGUGACAUCAUACUCGUGAUGGAAAUCAAGGACAGCAACAACAGGAUCUGCCCCAUACUGAUGGAGAAGCUGAACAGAAAUUCAAGGAGAGGCAUAACGUACAACUAUGUGAUUAGCUCUCGGCUUGGAAGAAACACAUAUAAAGAACAAUAUGCCUUUCUCUACAAGGAAAAGCUGGUGUCUGUGAAGAGGAGUUAUCACUACCAUGACUAUCAGGAUGGAGACGCAGAUGUGUUUUCCAGGGAGCCCUUUGUGGUCUGGUUCCAAUCUCCCCACACUGCUGUCAAAGACUUCGUGAUUAUCCCCCUGCACACCACCCCAGAGACAUCCGUUAAGGAGAUCGAUGAGUUGGUUGAGGUCUACACGGACGUGAAACACCGCUGGAAGGCGGAGAAUUUCAUUUUCAUGGGUGACUUCAAUGCCGGCUGCAGCUACGUCCCCAAGAAGGCCUGGAAGAACAUCCGCUUGAGGACUGACCCCAGGUUUGUUUGGCUGAUCGGGGACCAAGAGGACACCACGGUGAAGAAGAGCACCAACUGUGCAUAUGACAGGAUUGUGCUUAGAGGACAAGAAAUCGUCAGUUCUGUUGUUCCCAAGUCAAACAGUGUUUUUGACUUCCAGAAAGCUUACAAGCUGACUGAAGAGGAGGCCCUGGAUGUCAGCGACCACUUUCCAGUUGAAUUUAAACUACAGUCUUCAAGGGCCUUCACCAACAGCAAAAAAUCUGUCACUCUAAGGAAGAAAACAAAGAGCAAACGCUCCUAGACCCAAGGGUCUCAUCUUAUUAACCAUUUCUUGCCUCUAAAUAAAAUGUCUCUAACAGAUAUGAACUGCUCCCUGUACUUAGGAAACAAGAGUGAUCCAACUGCUUUCAUUUUUUGACCUGAAUUUAUUCUGACUUGAGCCAAAUUGGAAGGAGAAUCUUUUGUAUCUCUCUUGGUCUCAUACCUCCCCUGAAUUGUCUAAAAGGGAACCAGGGGCAUUUGUAGACCAAAAUGAUGAUCUUCAUGCCCUGAGCCAGAGCCCCAUCCACUGUCACUGGCCCUGCUCAACCCUGUCAUGCGAGAGGCUGCAGGGGGAGGAAGAGCGUCAGCUUUCAGUCCUCAUGAGGGGUCCUGUUCCACACGCAAUGACCAGAAACACCAAGGCCCCAGCUGCCCCUGUGAUUUGGGCAAUUAACUGUUUUAAGAGUCUG